GCUGUACCGGAACGUGGGGCGAGGCGGUGAGUGUGGCCUCCUGGCCUCUUUUUCCUUUCCUGAUUCCUUGUGUAUGUGUGGCUGGGCCGCCCCUCUUCUCGGCUCAGAGUCACGGAGUGCCUUGAACUAGGCCCACCUCGCCGGGGCGGCUGGUUCUCUGUUUGUGGGACGCUGGUGUCUCUGGAGGCCCUUCCUGAGAAGCCGUCGCCAGAGUUACGUCGCGGUUUUCUUAACUUUAGAGCCUGGGGGCCGGAGACCCUGAUUGCACUCGACCUGGCUCUGCCCUACUCUCUGCGUGACUUCCAGGAUACAGCAGGACUCAAGUCUCGUGGCGAUGACAGCCUUCAAUCAAACAUCCAAAACUGCAGUUGUGAUCAUUGAGACGGAAAGGUACAAGGCACCCCAGAUUAUAUCACAGGAGACCUGACCUAGCCCCAGGGCAAGGAACCUUUACUGAGGAGCUGUUCAUCAAAGAAAAAGGGUUCUUUUGGUCACCCACCACUGGCCCCAUGGCUGCCGUGCAGAUGGAUCCUGAGCUAGCCAAGCGCCUCUUCUUUGAAGGGGCCACUGUGGUCAUCCUGAACAUGCCCAAGGGAACAGAGUUUGGGAUUGACUAUAACUCCUGGGAGGUCGGGCCCAAGUUCCGGGGCGUGAAGAUGAUCCCUCCAGGCAUCCACUUCCUCCACUACAGCUCUGUGGACAAGGCUAAUCCGAAGGAAGUAGGCCCUCGUAUGGGUUUCUUCCUUAGCCUGCACCAGCGGGGGCUGACAGUGCUGCGCUGGAGCACACUCAGGGAAGAGGUAGACCUGUCCCCAGCCCCAGAGUCUGAGGUGGAGGCCAUGAGGGCCAACCUCCAGGAGCUGGACCAGUUCCUGGGGCCUUACCCAUAUGCCACCCUGAAGAAGUGGAUCUCACUCACCAACUUCAUCAGCGAAGCCACAGUGGAGAAGCUACAGCCCGAGAAUCGACAGAUCUGUGCCUUUUCCGAUGUGCUACCUGUGCUCUCCAUGAAGCACACCAAGGACCGCGUGGGGCAGAAUCUACCCCGCUGUGGCAUUGAGUGCAAAAGCUACCAAGAGGGCCUGGCCCGGCUACCAGAGAUGAAGCCCAGAGCCGGGACAGAGAUCCGCUUCUCAGAGCUGCCCACGCAGAUGUUCCCAGAGGGUGCCACGCCAGCUGAGAUAACCAAGCACAGCAUGGACCUGAGCUAUGCCCUGGAGACUGUGCUCAACAAGCAGUUCCCCAGCAGCCCCCAGGAUGUGCUUGGUGAACUCCAGUUUGCUUUUGUGUGCUUCCUGCUGGGGAAUGUGUACGAGGCAUUUGAGCAUUGGAAGCGGCUCCUGAACCUCCUGUGCCGGUCAGAAGCAGCCAUGAUGAAGCACCACACCCUCUACAUCAACCUCAUCUCCAUCCUGUACCACCAGCUUGGUGAGAUCCCCGCUGACUUCUUCGUAGACAUUGUCUCCCAAGACAACUUCCUCACCAGCACCUUACAGGUUUUCUUUUCCUCUGCCUGCAGCAUUGCCGUGGAUGCCACCCUGAGAAAGAAAGCUGAAAAGUUCCAAGCUCACCUGACCAAGAAGUUCCGGUGGGACUUUGCUGCGGAACCUGAGGACUGUGCCCCGGUGGUGGUGGAGCUCCCUGAGGGCAUCGAGAUGGGCUAACUCGGGGAGCGCUCUCAGCUGCGAGGGGCCCCUUCCCACAGGGCUGCAGUCCUGGCCUCUCCAUUUACUUCUUCCCAUCCUGGGACCUGCCAGGGCAGCAAUCUCUCCAGGUCCUGCAAAGAUGGAGCCAGAAUUCCCUUUUUCACUGAUAAAUAUAUUUCUUCAUUGCCAAAGAGGCUGUACCCAUCCUGAAGGCACAUUUGUGGGUUCCCCAUCAGCCAGGCCUUGGUGCUAACCUGGCUGAAUUUCACACAGGCUCUUACACACACACGCUCCUAGGAGACAUCUGCCUACACGGCAACCAUAUUUCCUCUGAAUGAGAAGGAAUUGAACCAAAAGUCCAAGAAAGAACUGAUUGCUUGUUCCAUAGGAGCUUAGGAAACAAGAAACCCUGGAUUGCCCAGGGGGUCUGAGAAGUUGGUUGGUGACUUUUUUUGCGGUUAAAUGAAGGGUGAUGGGGAGAUCAGCCCGAAUUGCCGCCUGCCUCUUGCUAAAUAGGAGCAGAGGACUUGGCCUGCAGCUCCUUGGGAGCCCUUGAUUGGGAAGAGAGUUUCAAGGGAGGCAGCUGGAUUCAAUCUAGCAGGUGGUCAGCUUCAGCUUUCUCCAUCGAAAUCCCAUUCUCCUGUCCAGAGGCCCAGUGGGUCAUCUCCCAAGGUGGGUGUGGACCCUGGCCUCAGAGGCCUUGCUGGUGCUGUCACCUCCCACCUGUUCCAUUCCGAGGCCUCACCCAGAAGUGGGACCCUCCCCUUCCUCACCAGAGCCACCGUGACUGUUUCUGAUGACCUGGAGAGUCAACAACAACCAGAAAGGUUUCUGCCCAGAGCAGGCUUCUUAAGGCCUUUACGAAGUUUUGUGCCUUCCAAGUGCUGAAGAAGACCUGGUCAGCCUAAAUCUUCCCAGUCCCGCUGUGGAGCUGUCAGUCACCGGAGUAAUGAGCUCCUGGUUCCUCGGGAGUCCUUCGUGCUGUGUGGCAGGGUUCCUCUCUAGACAAGUACACAGGCCCUGCCACCCUGACAUCAAACUGUUGUACUAUGAUCACAGUCCCUGUGCCAUCCUUUUCCAAGACUGGGGCUCACACCAUGUUUUUGAAUGAGAAUCCCUGCUGGUUGAGACUUUUGCUUCCACUUGUUUCCUUGGAGAUGUUUUUCCAAGAGCAUAAUGUACAUUAAAGUCUUCGAGUUGAGACAA